ACUUUGCCCUGAGCACUCCUGCAGGGGUAGAAGACUCCAGAACCUUCUCUCAGGCCCAUGGCCCAAGCAGCCCAUGGAACUUCAUAACCUGAGCUCUCCAUCUCCCUCUCUCUCCUCCUCUGUUCUCCCUCCCUCCUUCUCUCCCUCACCCUCCUCUGCUCCCUCUGCCUUUACCACUGUGGGGGGGUCCUCUGGAGGGCCCUGCCACCCCACCUCUUCCUCGCUGGUGUCUGCCUUCCUGGCACCAAUCCUGGCCCUGGAGUUUGUCCUGGGCCUGGUGGGGAACAGUUUGGCCCUCUUCAUCUUCUGCAUCCACACGCGGCCCUGGACCUCCAACACGGUGUUCCUGGUCAGCCUGGUGGCCGCUGACUUCCUCCUGAUCAGCAACCUGCCCCUCCGCGUGGACUACUACCUCCUCCAUGAGACCUGGCGCUUUGGGGCUGCUGCCUGCAAAGUCAACCUCUUCAUGCUGUCCACCAACCGCACGGCCAGCGUUGUCUUCCUCACAGCCAUCGCACUCAACCGCUACCUGAAGGUGGUGCAGCCCCACCACGUGCUGAGCCGUGCUUCCGUGGGGGCAGCUGCCCGGGUGGCCGGGGGACUCUGGGUGGGCAUCCUGCUCCUCAACGGGCACCUGCUCCUGAGCACCUUCUCCGGCCCCUCCUGCCUCAGCUACAGGGUGGGCACGAAGCCCUCGGCCUCGCUCCGCUGGCACCAGGCACUGUACCUGCUGGAGUUCUUCCUGCCACUGGCGCUCAUCCUCUUUGCUAUUGUGAGCAUUGGGCUCACCAUCCGGAACCGUGGUCUGGGCGGGCAGGCAGGCCCGCAGAGGGCCAUGCGUGUGCUGGCCAUGGUGGUGGCCGUCUACACCAUCUGCUUCUUGCCCAGCAUCAUCUUUGGCAUGGCUUCCAUGGUGGCUUUCUGGCUGUCCGCCUGCCGAUCCCUGGACCUCUGCACACAGCUCUUCCAUGGCUCCCUGGCCUUCACCUACCUCAACAGUGUCCUGGACCCCGUGCUCUACUGCUUCUCUAGCCCCAACUUCCUCCACCAGAGCCGGGCCUUGCUGGGCCUCACGCGGGGCCGGCAGGGCCCAGUGAGCGACGAGAGCUCCUACCAACCCUCCAGGCAGUGGCGCUACCGGGAGGCCUCUAGGAAGGCGGAGGCCAUAGGGAAGCUGAAAGUGCAGGGCGAGGUCUCUCUGGAAAAGGAAGGCUCCUCCCAGGGCUGAGGGCCAGCUGCAGGGCUGCAGCGCUGUGGGGGUAAGGGCUGCCGCGCUCUGGCCUGGAGGGACAAGGCCAGCACACGGUGCCUCAACCAACUGGACAAGGGAUGGCGGCAGACCAGGGGCCAGGCCAAAGCACUGGCAGGACUCAGGUGGGUGGCAGGGAGAGAAACCCACCUAGGCCUCUCAGUGUGUCCAGGAUGGCAUUCCCAGAAUGCAGGGGAGAGCAGGAUGCCGGGUGGAGGAGACAGGCAAGGUGCCGUUGGCACACCAGCUCAGACAGGGGCCUGCGCAGCUGCAGGGGACAGACGCCAAUCACUGUCACAGCAGAGUCACCUUAGAAAUUGGACAGCUGCAUGUUCUGUGCUCUCCAGUUUGUCCCUUCCAAUAUUAAUAAACUUCCCUUUUAAAUAUA